AACGCAAAACCUGCUCUUUAGAUUUCGAGCUUAUUCUCUUCUAGCAGUUUCUUGCCACCAUGUCGGAAACCGCUCCUGCCGAGACAGCCACCCCAGCGCCGGUGGAGAAAUCCCCGGCUAAGAAGAAGGCAACUAAGAAGGCUGCCGGCGCCGGCGCUGCUAAGCGCAAAGCGACGGGGCCCCCAGUCUCAGAGCUGAUCACCAAGGCUGUGGCUGCUUCUAAGGAGCGCAAUGGCCUUUCUUUGGCAGCCCUUAAGAAGGCCUUAGCGGCCGGUGGCUACGACGUGGAGAAGAAUAACAGCCGCAUUAAGCUGGGCCUCAAGAGCUUGGUGAGCAAGGGCACCCUGGUGCAGACCAAGGGCACUGGUGCUUCUGGCUCCUUUAAACUCAACAAGAAGGCGGCCUCCGGGGAAGCCAAGCCCAAAGCCAAGAAGGCAGGCGCCGCUAAAGCUAAGAAGCCCGCGGGGGCCACGCCUAAGAAGGCCAAGAAGGCUGCAGGGGCGAAAAAGGCAGUGAAGAAGACUCCGAAGAAGGCGAAGAAGCCCGCGGCGGCUGGCGUCAAAAAGGUGGCGAAGAGCCCUAAGAAGGCCAAGGCCGCUGCCAAACCGAAAAAGGCAACCAAGAGUCCUGCCAAGCCCAAGGCAGUUAAGCCGAAGGCGGCAAAGCCCAAAGCCGCUAAGCCCAAAGCAGCAAAACCUAAAGCUGCAAAGGCCAAGAAGGCGGCUGCCAAAAAGAAGUAGGAAGCUGGCGUGUGAAAACCGCAACAAAGCCCCAAAGGCUCUUUUCAGAGCCACCCA